GUCCCCUCAGGUGUCCUGCAGGCACAGCUCCUCGGGGGGCCCAGGCCGAUGGCAGGUCUUAACGUGUCCCUCUCCUUCUUCUUUGCCACCUUCGCCCUCUGUGAGGCGGCCAGGCGGGCCUCCAAGGCCCUGCUCCCAGUGGGCGCCUAUGAAGUCUUCGCCCGGGAGGCGAUGAGGACGCUGGUCGAGCUCGGGCCCUGGGCUGGGGACUUUGGGCCUGACCUGCUGCUCACCCUGCUCUUCCUGCUCUUCCUGGCGCACGGGGUCACCUUGGACGGGGCCUCGGCCAACCCCACUGUGUCCCUGCAGGAGUUCCUCAUGGCCGAGCAGUCUCUGCCUGGCACGCUGUUGAAGCUGGCGGCACAGGGGCUGGGCAUGCAGGCCGCCUGCACCCUGAUGCGCCUCUGCUGGGCCUGGGAGCUCAGUGACCUGCACCUGCUGCAGAGCCUCAUGGCCCAGAGCUGCAGCUCGGCCCUGCGCACAUCCGUGCCCCACGGGGCGCUUGUGGAGGCCGCCUGCGCCUUUUGUUUCCAUCUGACCCUCCUGCACCUGCGGCACAGUCCUCCCGCCUACAGCGGGCCCGCUGUGGCUCUGUUGGUCACCGUCACGGCCUACACGGCCGGGCCCUUCACGUCUGCCUUCUUCAACCCUGCCCUGGCCGCCUCUGUGACCUUUGCCUGCUCGGGACACACCUUACUGGAGUACGUGCAGGUGUACUGGCUGGGCCCUCUGACAGGGAUGGUCCUGGCUGUGCUGCUGCACCAGGGCCGCCUUCCCCACCUUUUCCAGAGGAACCUGUUCUACGGCCAGAAGAACAAGUACCGAGCACCCCGAGGGAAGCCGGCCCCGGCCUCAGGGGACACCCAGACCCCUGCAAAGGGGUCCAGUGUCCGGGAGCCUGGGCGCAGUGGUGUUGAGGGGCCACAUUCCAGCUGAGUGGCCUUGCUCUGUGUGAGCCCCGUGCGAGGGCCCUGCUUGUAGCUGGACCCUGGAACCUUCUGUAGCUAAGAGGGAAUCCUGGCCCCCUCCCCAGAAGCCAUUUGUCAAUAAACCAUUUCUAAGA